GCCCUCCGUCCAUUCCUUUAGUGCUGCGCCGACAGCGGUCAGGAUCUCGGCUUUCUUGCUUCGAGAGGGACUAGGUGCCUCCACCAGAGCUUCUGUCGCUCUGUAACCUGCACUGUGACCUACACUAGUCGCGGGAGCCACGCAGAGGACGCCGGAACACCCUGGAAGCCGAGAAAUGAUCAUGCUUUUUGUGUUGUGUGUGAAAUCUUAUUGCCAAAUCAAGGUCGUCUUGGUUUUGACAAGUGUGAAAUUGUGAGUUUUGCAUUUUCCAUAUAAGUAAACGAUUCAUUAGGAAGUAGUUUUGUAAAAGGUGCAGUUCUGUGUCUAAUUCAUUUCUUUGCAUUUGCUAAUUCAGGUGUUUCAAUACCAUUUGUUUUGUGCCACCAUGUCUAAUUUUUUAUUUUAUUAUGGAGACGGGUAUCUCCUUAUGUUGCCCAGGCUGGUCUCGAACUGCGGGGCUCAAAUGAUCUGUCCGCCUUGGCCUCCAGCUUGCAUUUUUAAUACACGUCUUUAUAGUAGAUUUUUCUGUGUUCCUAGUGCCUCUCUUGUCAUCUUAUGGAAUCUUCUCUUAUAUAUUUAGUUUAUUGAGUGUUUCUAAUCAUCAGGAGAUAUUAACUUAUUUAUGCUGGAGGUUGCACUUUUUUGAAUUGCCGACGUGUGAAAAAUCAGACUUUGGCCAUGACCUUGAGCAGUAGGAUAUAAAUAACUCCCACAUGCUUAGCGUUCCAAAAAUGGAACACUAGGCAUAAAUUGGUUAAGGCUUGUCAGAUGCCUUUUCUGCCUCUAUUAAGGACAUUCUUGUGGUGUUUUGUUUGUUUGUUUAAAGAUAGAGUCUCACUCUGUUGCCCCGGCUGGAGUGCAGUAGCGCAAUCUCGGCUCACUGCAACCUCUGCCUCCCAGAUUCAAAUGAUUCUCCACGUCCCAGUCAAGUGACUGGGACUACAUGUGCCACCACGCCUGGCUAAUUUUUGUAUUUUUUAGAGAUGGAGUUCCACCACGUUGGCCAGGCUGGUCUCAAACUGCUGACCUCAAGUGAUCUUCCCACCUCAACCUCCCAAAGUGCUGGGAUUAUAGGCAUGAGCCACCAUGCCUGGCUGCUACCAUGAUUUAUUAUCAUUACUUAUCUUAAAACAAAAUGUAAAACUUAUCAGCUUAAGAAAUUUUACAUGUACAGUUGAGAUAGUUUGACAAAUCUACAUAAGUUCUCUAAGAUGAAUUCUAUUGUAUUUUGCUUUUUUCAAUUAUCCCGAGGUGUCAUGCAUGUUGUAGUUUAGUCCAAGAUGUUAUUUUUUCUUUUUCUUUUUUUUUUUUUUUGAAUCAAGUUUCACUCUUGUUGCCCAGGCUGGAGUGCAAUGGUGCAAUCUUGGCUCACCACAACCUCCACCUCCCAGCUUCAAGCAAUUCUCCUGCCUCAGCCUCCUGAGUAGCUGGGUUUACAGGAAAGCGCCAUUACACCCGGAUAAUUUUGUAUUUUUAGUAGAAAUGGGGUUUCUCCAUGCUGGUCAGGCUGAUCUUGAACUCCAACCCUCAGGUGAUCUGCCUACCUUGGCCUUCCAAAGUGCUGGGAUUACAGGCAUGAGCCACCACGCCUGGCUAAGAUGUCAUUUUCUAAGAGUAAAUAAUAUCCCAUUUUAUGUAUAUGCUUACCACAUUUUGUUUUUACAUUCAGCCAUCAAUGGAUAUGUGGGUGGCUGCAUUGCUCAUUACUGCCACCUCAGGAAGGUCGUAUAGUGGUUAAAUCUGUGCUUAUGAUACCUGGGUAUCUCUUAGGAGUUUCUUGUUUGCCCUCUUGUGUACAUACGGUGCCAGGUUUUGCUUAGGAAUGUCCCCUUUGCCCUAUCAGCAUCUAUCUAGCUACAUUCUGACAGGAUAACUGCAAAGUGAAUGAUUCCUGGGCAUCAUAAUGGAAGUUUCUUUCUACCUAGGUGAUUCCCCUCCUCUCUGCUUAUAUCUAGCAUGCCUGAUUUGGGUGGUCCCUGGGGGUGUGGGAUUUCCCAGGGGCUCCCCCUCCUGCUCUUUGCUACCUACAUGCUUCCUCUGACAAUAUCAUCAAAGAUUACACUUUGAGAACAGGCAUUUUCAAGGAUACACAGCCUCAGGACUGCUAAUGUUAACUUUGUUUUGCCUAUGAAUUCGUAGGACUCUAUCAUGACAGGUGCUACAGACCCACAGUCCAAAGAGACAUUAGGGACAGCCCAGGCAACCCGCUUUUCUCCCUGGGUUCGGUAAAUACAUUUCCUAUCCUGCUGUGGCUUUAGCCCUUGUUCAGUUCUAGCAUCACAAUUGCUUUAUGAACUAGCCAGGUGUGGUGGCACAUGCCUGUGGUCUCAACUACUCAGGAGGCUGAGGCAUGAGAAUUGCAUGAACCCAGGAGUAAGAGGUUGUAGUGAGCCAAGAUGGUGCCACUACACUCCAGCCUGGGUAACAGAAUGAGACGCUGUCUUAAAAAAAAAAACAACUGCUAGCUGGGCAUGGUGGCUCAUGCCUGUAAUCCCAGAACUUUGGGAGCCUGAGGCAGGCAGAUCACCUGAGGUCGGCAGCCUGACCAACGUGGAGAGACUCUGUCUCUACUAAAAAUACAACAUUAGCCAGGCAUGGUGGCAUAUGCCUGUAAUCUUAGCUACUCAGGAGGCUGAGGAAGAAGAAGUGCUAGAACCCCGGCAGUGAGCCGAGAUCAUGCCAUUGCACUGCAGCCUGGGCAACAAGAGUGAAAAAAAAAACAAGUUGCUUUGUGGAAGAAAGUAAGUAUACACAGGGAGAAAGAGAUCUGAUGACCAAAGCAGGGAAUACGUGUUUGGAGUCCACGGCAUCCUGAGAACUUCUUGGGAAUAGAGUCUAGGCCCCCAGUGCUGUCACUCUCACCCAUCUUCUUCUACACAUGUGAGAUGUUUCAGGACCCAGUGGCUUUUAAGGAUGUGGCUGUGAACUUCACCCAGGAGGAGUGGGCUUUGCUGGAUAUUUCCCAGAGGAAACUCUACAGGGAAGUGAUGCUGGAAACUUUCAGGAACCUGACCUCUUUAGGAAAAAGGUGGAAAGACCAGAACAUUGAAUAUGAGCACCAAAACCCCAGGAGAAACUUCAGGAGUCUCAUAGAAGAAAAAGUCAAUGAAAUUAAAGAUGACAGUCAUUGUGGAGAAACUUUUACCCCAGUUCCAGAUGACAGACUGAACUUCCAGGAGAAGAAAGCUUCUCCUGAAGUAAAAUCAUGUGAAAGCUUUGUGUGUGGAGAAGUUGGCCUAGGUAACUCAUCUUUUAAUAUGAACAUCAGAGGUGACAUUGGACACAAGGCAUAUGAGUAUCAGGAAUAUGGACCAAAGCCAUGUAAGUGUCAACAACCUAAAAAAGCCUUCAGAUACCGCCCCUCCUUUAGAACACAAGAAAGGGAUCACACUGGAGAGAAACCCAAUGCUUGUAAAGUAUGUGGAAAAACCUUUAUUUCCCAUUCAAGUGUUCGAAGACACAUGGUAAUGCACAGUGGGGAUGGACCUUAUAAAUGUAAGUUUUGUGGGAAAGCAUUCCAUUGUCUCAGAUUAUAUCUUAUCCAUGAAAGAAUUCACACUGGAGAGAAACCAUGUGAAUGUAAACAGUGUGGUAAAUCCUUUAGUUAUUCUGCUACCCAUCGAAUACAUAAAAGAACUCACACUGGAGAAAAGCCUUAUGAAUAUCAGGAGUGUGGGAAAGCAUUUCAUAGUCCCAGAUCCUAUCGUAGACAUGAAAGGAUUCACAUGGGAGAAAAGGCUUAUCAAUGUAAGGAAUGUGGAAAAGCAUUCACGUGUCCCCGUUAUGUUCGUAUACAUGAAAGGACCCACUCUAGGAAAAAUCUCUAUGAAUGUAAGCAGUGUGGGAAAGCAUUAUCCUCUCUUACAAGUUUUCAAACACACGUAAGAUUGCACUCUGGAGAAAGACCUUAUGAAUGUAAGAUAUGUGGAAAAGACUUUUGUUCUGUGAAUUCAUUUCAAAGACAUGAAAAAAUUCACAGUGGAGAGAAACCCUAUAAAUGUAAGCAGUGUGGUAAAGCCUUCCCUCAUUCCAGUUCCCUUCGAUAUCAUGAAAGGACUCACACUGGAGAGAAACCCUAUGAGUGUAAGCAAUGUGGGAAAGCCUUCAGAUCUGCCUCACACCUUCGAGUGCAUGGUAGGACUCACACUGGAGAGAAACCGUAUGAAUGUAAGGAAUGUGGGAAAGCCUUCAGAUAUGUGAAUAACCUUCAAAGUCAUGAAAGGACACAAACACACAUAAGAAUACACUCUGGAGAAAGACGUUAUAAAUGUAAGAUAUGUGGGAAAGGCUUUUAUUGUCCCAAAUCAUUUCAAAGACAUGAAAAAACUCACACUGGAGAGAAACUCUAUGAAUGCAAGCAACGUUCAGUAGUUCCUUCAGUAGUUCCAGUUCCUUUUGAUAUCAUGAAAGGACUCACACUGGAGAGAAGCCCUAUAAAUGCGAGCAAUGUGGGAAAGCCUUCAGAGCUGUGUCAAUCCUUUGAAUGCAUGGUAGGACUCACCCUGAAGAGAAACCCUAUGAGUGUGAGCAAUGACGGAAAGCCUUCAGAUCUGCCCCACACCUUUGAAUACGUGGUAGGACACACAAUGGAGAGAAGCCCUAUGCAUGUAAGGAAUGUGGGAAACCCUUCGGAUCUGCCCAGAACCUUCGAAUUCAUGAAAGGACACAAACACACAUAAUGCACUCUGUAGAGAGACCUUAUAAAUGUAAGAUAUGUGGGAGGGGCUUUUAUUCUGCCAAGUCAUUUCAAAUACAUGAAAAAUCUUACACUGGAGAGAAACCCUAUGAGUGUAAGCAAUGUGGGAAAGCCUUUGUUUCCUUCACUUCCUUUCGAUAUCAUGAAAGGACUCACACUGGAGAGAACCCCUAUGAGUGUAAGCAAUUUGGGAAAGCCUUCAGAUCUGUCAAAAAUCUUCGAUUUCAUAAAAGGACACACACUGGAGAGAAACCCUGUGAAUGUAAGAAAUGUAGAAAAGCAUUCCAUAAUUUCUCUUCUUUGCAAAUACAUGAAAGGAUGCACAGAGGAGAGAAGCUCUGUGAAUGUAAGCAUUGUGGGAAAGCAUUCAUAUCUGCCAAGAUCCUUUGAAUACAUGCAAGAACACACAAUGGAGAGAAACCCUAUGAAUGUAAAGAAUGCAGAAAAGCAUUCAGCUUGCCUACUUCCUUUCAUAGACAUGAAAAGACUCACACUGGAAGGAAACACUAUGAAUGCAAGCAAUGUGGCAAAGCUUUCACUUCUUCCAGUUCUUUUCAAUAUCAUGAAAGAACACACUAGGGAGAAACCCUAUCAAUGUAAGCAAUGUGCAAAAGCCUUUAUUUCUUCCACUUCUUUUCAAUAUCAUGAAAGGACUCACAUGGGAGAGAAACCCUAUGAGUGUAUGCCAAGUGGGAAAGCCUUCAUUUCUUCUAGUUCCCUUCAAUAUCAUGAAAGGACUCACACUGGAGAGAAGCCCUAUGAAUAUAAGCAAUGUGGGAAAGCCUUCAGAUCAGCCUCGCACCUUCAAAUGCAUGGAAGGACUCACACUGGAGAAAAACCCUAUGAAUGUAAGCAGUAUGGGAAAGCGUUCAGACCUGACAAGAUUCUUUGAAUACAGAUAAUGAAUGUAAACAAUUAACUGUUUAUAAUAACUGUAUACUAACAAAUGAUAUUCUUUUUAAAUAAGAAGCUAUAAUAUCCCAUUGGUGUCAUGUAUUAGAUCAGCCUUAUACUGUUAAAUUGUUAUUAUUUGGACAUUGUGAGUCAGUAUAACCAUGUGGAUAAAAUGCCAGACAUCUUUUUAUUCGAAAAUUUUACUUUUCAUGCUUCUGUACUUACAUUUUUAUCUCAACCUUAAUUUUUCUUUCUUUUUUUUUUUCCCCCAGAAAGAAUCUCACUCUGUCACCCAGGCUGGAGUGCAGUGGCAUGAUCUCAGGUCACUGCAACCUCUGCCUCCAGGGUUCAAGCAAUUCUCCUGCCUCAGUCUCCUGAGUAGCUGGGACUACAGGCAUGCGCCACCAUGCCAGGCUAAUUUUUUGUAUUUUUUAGUAGAGACGGGGUUUCACCAUAUUGGCUAGGCUGGUCUCAAACUCCAGACCUCAUGAUUUACCCACCUCGGCCUCCCAAAAUGCUGGGAUUACAGACAUGAACCAUCAUGCCCAGCUGCAACCCUAAUUUUUCAUUCAGUCAUAAUACCAAUAGUUAUCUCAUGCACCUCUGAGUGCCUUCUUCCCCAAAACCAGCAGUGCCAUACCUGCUGUCAGCAAGGGUGUAAUAUACCAUAGUGAUAAAUAUGACCAAAAGCCAUAAAUGACUGUGAGAUGUAUGAGAAUUACAAGUCACAUUAGUAAGAAGAGAAAAAUUUUGGUCAUGUUUAUGAUUUGAAAUACGUUUUCCUCUAUCACAUUUAAAAAUAUAGUUACAAAAUGCCCUUGUUUUUGUCCUGAUUCAUCAUGGUCACUGAGGAGCAUCGUCUCAUAUGCCUGGUAUGUGACACGUGUCUCUCCAACAAUAAAAGACUUGGCCUUGGCUGGGCAUGGUGGCUCACGCCUGUAAUCCCAGCACUUUGGGAGGCCGAGGUCAGGAGUUAGAGACCAUUCUGACCAAUAUGAUCAAACCCCGUCUCUACUAAAAAUACAAAAGUUAGCAGGGCGUGGUGGCAUGCUCCUGUAAUCCUAGCUAUUCAGGAGGCUGACAUAGGAGAAUUGCUUGAAUAUAGGAAGCAGAGGUUGCAGUGAGCCGAGGUUGCACCAUUGUACUCCAGCCUGGGCAACAAGAGUGAAACUCUGUCUUAAAAAACACAAAAAAAGACUUGGCCUUAGGGCCGAGUGCGGUGGCUCACGCCUAUAAUCCCAGCACUUUGGGAGGCCGAGGCGGGCGGAUCACUAGGUCAGGAAAUGGAGACCAUCCUGGCCAACACAGUGAAACCCAGUCUCUACUAAAAAAUACAAAAAA